AACCCGACUCCGCUGUCUGCCCUCACAGGACCCAAACAUCCCUGGCCUAAUGUGGCUCAUCAAAACUUCAGCCUAGAUCUCGGAGGACCUUGAUCUGAGCAGGAUUCAUGGCAUGGAAUGUGGAGUCCCAGGACUGGCCAGCAGCGAAGUGAGGUUCUUGAGCAGGGCUCUGGCUCACGCUUGUAAUCCCAACAUUUUGGGAGGACGAAGCCAGCCUCAUCGCUUAAGCACAGGAGUUCGAGGACUGGGAGGUGGAGGUUGUGGCAGGGCUGUGGCUCACGCUUGUAAUCCCAACAUUUUGGGCGGAGGAAGCCAGCCUCAUCGCUUAAGCACAGGAGUUCGCGGACUGGGAGGCAGGGCUCUGGCUCACGCUUGUAAUCCCAACAUUUUGGGAGGACGAAGCCAGCCUCAUCGCUUAAGCACAGGAGUUCGAGGACUGGGAGGUGGAGGUUGUGGUGCCUGUAUCACCUGCCCUUCUGCUGACACUCCUGCCUGCUGUUCCUGACUACAGCCAUCAUGCCUCGGGGUCAGAAGAGUACGCUCCAUGCACGUGAGAAACGCCAGCAGACCCGGGGUCAGACCCAGGAUCACCAGGGUGCUCAGAUCACUGCAACUAACAAGAAAAAAGUAUCCUUUUCAUCCCCUCUUAUUUUGGGGGCUACUAUCCAGAAAAAGUCUGCUGGUAGGUCACGUAGUGCUCUCAAGAAGCCUCAGAGAGCACUAUCCACCACUACAUCUGUAGAUGUUUCUUACAAAAAGUCAUACAAGGGAGCCAACAGCAAAAUUGAGAAAAAGCAAAGCUUCUCUCAGGGUCUAUCCUCCACUGUGCAGUCUCGCACAGACCCUCUAAUCAUGAAGACAAAUAUGUUGGUGCAGUUCCUGAUGGAAAUGUACAAGAUGAAAAAGCCCAUUAUGAAAGCAGAUAUGCUAAAAAUUGUCCAAAAAAGCCAUAAGAAUUGCUUCCCUGAGAUCCUUAAAAAAGCUUCUUUCAACAUGGAGGUGGUAUUUGGUGUUGAUUUAAAGAAAGUUGAUUCUACCAAGGACUCCUAUGUCCUUGUCAGCAAAAUGGAUCUCCCCAACAAUGGGACAGUGACUCGUGGGAGGGGAUUUCCCAAGACAGGUCUCCUGCUGAAUCUCCUGGGCGUGAUCUUCAUGAAGGGCAACUGUGCCACUGAGGAGAAGAUCUGGGAAUUCCUGAAUAAGAUGAGAAUAUAUGAUGGGAAGAAACACUUCAUAUUUGGGGAGCCCAGAAAGCUCAUCACCCAAGAUUUGGUGAAGCUUAAAUACCUGGAGUACCGACAAGUGCCCAACAGUAAUCCUGCACGCUAUGAAUUCCUGUGGGGUCCAAGAGCCCAUGCUGAAACCAGCAAGAUGAAGGUCCUGGAGUUUUGGGCCAAGGUCAAUAAAACUGUCCCCAGUGCGUUCCAGUUCUGGUAUGAAGAGGCUUUGAGAGAUGAGGAAGAAAGAGUCCAAGCUGCAGCUAUGCUCAAUGAUGGCAGUAGUGCCAUGGGCAGAAAGUGUUCCAAGGCCAAGGCUAGCAGCUCUUCCCACGCCUAGUGAAGUUGAAGCAAAUUUUGCAUUUUGUGGUUAAAGAGGGCAGUCACUGUUCCAAGGAGUGAAGGACUGGGUGUUACUGGAGGGAACACACUGUAUAAUACCUUUUGUUUCUGUUCUAAAUGGAUAAUUUGAAGUUUUAUCUGUAUUUUGGGGCAUAUUUUUCAAAUGUUCCUUUUAUUUAACAUUGUAAUCUAAGUUUAGGAUUGAUACUGGUCACAUUUGUUGUUUAAGAGUAAAAAUUUUGCUGUUUUGUAAAACAGAUUGAGAAAAAUUCGAUCUUAUUUAGUGAUCUGUUGCAAGAUAACUUGGAAUUAGAAUAAGCAUUUCCUUGAAAAUGUUUAAAAAAAAAAAGUCAGCAGUAAAAUGUAUGGCAUUAAGAAAUAGAGAAAGAGUGUAAGAUGGUCAAUAUUUGGUUUCCUAAAUGCUUUUACUCUGUGCUUUAAGAAAAUGAAAGAUAAAUAACCAUAUAUGUCUGGCUUACUUAAGAAUGUAGAAUUAAAUCAUAAUAAAUUAGACCUCAUGCUGACACA